AUUGUCUCCACGGCGGCGAGGAGCGCCGGCGAGCGCAGCCCGGGACCGAGCGGGGCGGCGCGGCUGGCGGGGCCGGCGGCGGCUGAAGCGAGAGCGCGACGCGACGCGACCGCGGCUUCCCGAGCUGCGCCUGGCCGCCCAGCGCCGCGGCCCGCCCGAGGCCUGGAGGGGUCCGGGCCGCCGUCCAUGGUCGCGGCGUCCUGAGGCGGGGGACGCGCCCGGCGCCCCCGGCCCUCCUCCGCCUCCUCCCGCGGGGCGGGCGGCCUCCUCCGGCGCCUCCCCGCGCCCGCCCGCCGCUCGCCGCCGCCUCCCUCCCUCCUUCCCUGCGGCUCCCCCGGCUUUCGGAGCCCGGGGGCGGCCUGUGGCGCGCGGAGCCCGCGCCGGACUGCGCCUCUUUGGACCUUGAGGGGAAACAUGCGUUUGCCUUGGAUCGUUUGAAAUUCUGAGUUUGGGAUCCCCGCCCGCCCGCCUGCCUCUUCCGCCCCGCGGGUUUUUUCCUUUUUUCCUUUUGCUUUUUUUCCUUUUCUCCCUCCGGGUCUCCUUUUUGACUCCCUCCCCCUUUAUGCUCGCCCAGCCCUCCCCCUGCUGCUGAGAAGUGGGGGAGGGUCUCGGCCUCCAGGUUCCCGCCCCACCGGGGCCCGGGCGAGCAUGGGGGGCAAGCAGAGCACGGCGGCCCGCUCCCGGGGCCCCUUCCCGGGGGUCUCCACCGAUGACAGCGCCGUGCCGCCGCCGGGAGGGGCGCCCCAUUUCGGGCACUACCGGACGGGCGGCGGGGCCAUGGGGCUGCGCAGCCGCUCGGUCAGCUCGGUGGCAGGCAUGGGCAUGGACCCCAGCACGGCCGGGGGGGUGCCCUUUGGCCUCUACACCCCCGCCUCCCGGGGCACCGGCGACUCCGAGAGGGCGCCCGGCGGCGGAGGGUCUGCGUCCGACUCCACCUAUGCCCAUGGCAAUGGUUACCAGGAGACGGGCGGCGGUCACCAUAGAGACGGGAUGCUGUACCUGGGCUCCCGAGCCUCGCUGGCGGAUGCUCUACCUCUGCACAUCGCACCCAGGUGGUUCAGCUCGCAUAGUGAUGAAUCUUCGUGUGCAGCAUUGGUUCCAUCUCACCUGAAACAGACCAUGGGAUCUUCCAGGACAUCUGUUUCCUCUGUUACACAUUGCUGCAAGAAGCAAAACUUGUUUCUGCUUUGGAGCCUUUGAGUAAGGUCUAAGCAGCUUUUGCUCUUCUGUUGCAAGAUUGGAAGGGUAACGAUUUUGGUGCACAAUUAAUUAGAUGCCUGGAAGUUGAUAUGAUAUGUUUGCUUGUGUUUUCAAGGUGCUCUUGCAACUCUUCAUGGGCACAGAAAACAGUUGUCAGUGAAAUACAUGAGGGAGUUCAGUGUAUACAAGGCCUUCUCAGAGAGCGUGGGCUUAGGCUGGGUCUGGAGGUAGAAUACUGAAGGGCCCUGGUCCCAGCUACUCCUCUGAGCAGCUGUGACCUUGGGCAAGACAUAUCCCCUCUCUUGAGCCUUAUCUUUGUCGUUUUUAAAAUAGUUGUGGUCACCCUCACGAGCUCCAGCCUUGCUCCGCAAAUCCCGGGAGAGGAAGCGCUGUAGUCACAUUUGUCUUCUCUAGGUUCCUGACUUCCCUGUGCUGUGACCCCCACGUAUACCAUUCCCUAAUCCUAGAGUGCUUUUCUCUCCGUUCUUCACACGAAUUUCUCUUUCUGAUCCCUUAGGGCUUAGAGACCACUCUUAAAAAUUGGCCCCUCCGGUUAUUCUCUCCAGUCACUCACCUGUUACCUUAAUCAUUCUUUUUUUUGAGACAGAGUUUCGCUCUUGUUGCCCAGGCUGGAGUGCAGUGGUGCGACCUCUGCUCACUGCAGUCUCCGCCUCCCGGGUUCAAGCAAUUCUCCUGCCUCAGCCUCCCGAGUAGCUGGGAUUACUGGCAUGCGCCACCAUGCCCAAUAAGCUUGGGGCUAAUUUUGUUUUUUGUAGAGACGGGAUUUCUCCAUGUUUAUCAGGCUGGUCUCAAACUCCCGACCUCAGGUGAUCUGCCUGACCCGGCCUCCCAAAGUGAUAGGAUUACAGGCGUGAGCCACUGCGCCCUGCACCUUAAUCAUUCUUAACACACUUUGUAAGUAUUUUAUCUGUUUACUUUUUUCUGUGUAUGGUUUGCCUAAAGUCUAAGCUCCGUGAGAGCAGGACUGUGUUCCUUGAUCUCUGUUGUGGGUCCUGCACUGUGCCUGCCACUCACAUUUUUUGAGUACAUGAAUUUGAGUACUUUAUGUUCAUCAUCUCACUUAAUCAUCACUCUGACUCUAUGGAGUAAGACUGUUCUCUCCCACCCCCAUUGUGCAGGUAAGGAAACAGGUUUGGGGAGGUUAAGGAACUCACACAAGAUCAGGUGGUUAGUAGGUGGUGGAGAUGGGAUUGGAAUGCAGGUUGGCUGGUGCCAGAACCUGGGCUCUUAACCAGUACCCUCUUCCGCCUCUUAUCUGAAAACAUCACAAAGCCGCAUGGUGUCCUGGAGAUUGCGCUGGCCUACGAGUCAGAGUGCUAGGCUCAUCUCCUGGUUAGGCAGCUGAUUAGCUGCAUGAUUUGUGACCUUGGGCAAGCGAGUCAUUUAACCUCAGUCACAAUUUAUUCAUCUGUAAAAUGUAGAAGACGCCUGUCCUGCUUACCUCUCAGAGUCAUAGUGAGGGUCUCAUGAGAUAAUGUGCACAAAAGUCAAAGGACAUUCUAAAUGGAGAGUGGUGGAGUUCCUAUGGGGGCACUCUCUUAUAGUUGUCUGCCUUCAAUCGCCUCAGAUUUUUUUUUUUUUUCUUUUGAGACAGGGUCUUAUUCUGUCACCCAGGCUGGAGUGCAGUGGCGAGAUCAUAGCUCACUGCAGUCUCAGACUCCUGGGCUCAGUUGAUCCUCCCAGCUUGGCUUCCCAAAGUGCUGGGACCACAGGCAUGAGCCACCGUGCCAGGCCUAAUGGUCUCAGAAUUUGAUGGGUGGAGAGAGGUUUACAGCUGUGCUAGCUGUAGCCCCCAAAUGGAAUCUGGUUCUGUGUCCUAAAGUCUGGCCUGCAUUAGUGGGCUGCUUUUACUCAUAAUGCCGCUGAUAAGGGCUGCUUUAUAGAAGCAGAGUGACUCCCUUUCCACGUUAAAAAGUUUUGCUAUAACUCCUGAUGGCUGCCUCGGUGCUAUUCUGGAGGCCUGGUCAUUCUCUUUCGGUAGUUCUGUUUGUCUCAGAGUAUGGAUUUCUAAAUGUGGGGUACAAAACAUGCACCAUCCACCAUGUUGAAAGAAGUUGCUGUUUUCUAGGUUCUACUAUAAAAGGGCUGGCCAUUGAGGGCUUCACUUCACCUUCUUAGUCAUAUGUGUAUAUAUAUGUAUGCACUUUCAGAAAGUCUAAACUGUUCUUUAUUGUCAUCAAGCCAUCAACUGAGACUGAUACAAGGUGAUUGUGUUUUGUUUUUGUUAUUUAUUUAUUUUUGAGACAGGGUCUUGCUCUGUUGCCCAGGCUGGAGUGCCAUGGUGCAAUCAUGGUUCACUGUAGCCUCAAACUCUUGGGCUCAAGCCGUCUUCCCAUCUCAGCUUCCAGAGUAGCUGGGACUCAGGUGCGCACCACUACACCUGGCUAAAUUUUAUACAAUCUUUUGUAGAGAUGAGGUCUCACUAUGUUGCCUAGGCUGGCCUCAAACUCCGGGCUUUAAGCAAUCCUCCCACCUCAACCUCCCAAGGUAUUGGGAUUAUAGGCAUAAGCCACCACGCCUGGCCCAACGUGGCUUUUAAUAAGUCUUUGAACAUGCUAGGAGGUAUCUCUUGGGCUCUAUUUUGCUGCCACUGUAGGGUUCUCAAGUGAUUUAAUUUUCUUUUAUUGUUAGCUAAUGGGGGAGAAUUGCCAGCUCCCUUGGAGUGAAUCAGAAAGCCUUUGUGUCCCGCCAUAGGUGUGCUAGAAGUAAUGGGCCUUCACAUGGUUUCUGGAGAAGGAAAAGCAUUCUGUGGUCUCCAAAGAGCAUGAUGGGUCUCCUGCCCUGCAAAAGUUCUAUUGUUAAUGAAAACUUGUAUUAAAAAGCAGAAUUUUUAGCUCUUUAUUACCAUGAGGGCUUAUUUUCUUAAAAUACAAAAGUUACCCCGAGGCAAAGAUAAUUUCUUGAAGGUCAUAGUUAACUCUUGCUUAUUGAGGUUUGAAUGGUGUUGUAAGAAACAGUGGCUUAGCUCUUAAAGCGUUUGCUUUAUGGGAUACUACAUUUUGAUAUUAAACAAAGACCCACCUCAAUAUAUCAUGUCACAAGGAAUACUUAGGCCAUUCUUAGCCAAAGAAAUGAAGCAAGCUCUAGUUCCUUUUGGGAAAAGGAACAUGCUUUGUAUUUUACAUAUGUGGUAUUCACCCCAAGCUUAUUGGGCACAGAAAUUUGAGUAUAGUAGUUACUCCCUAUCCAAAGGGGAUUCGUUCCAAUACCCACAGUGGAUGCCUGAAACCGUGGAUAGUACCUCACCUGAACCCUAUAUCUACUAUGUCUUUUCCUGUAUAUACAUACCUUUGAUAAAGUUUUAUUUAUAAAUUAGGCACAAUAAAAGCUCGACAGCAGUAACUAAUAAUAGAACAAUUAUAACAAUAUACUGUGAUAAAAGUUAUGUGAAUGUGUUCUCUCUCUCUCUCUCCCUGUCUCGAAAGUACAGUCAUGCAUUGCUUAAUGACAGGGAUACUUUCUGAGAAAUGGGUCAUUAAGGGAUUUUGUCACUGGGCAAACAUCAUAGGGUGUACAUACACGGACCUAGGUGGUAUAGCCUGCUACAUACCUAGAUUAUAUGUUGCUCCUAGUGCUCCUAGGCUACAAACCUGUGCAACAUGUGACUGUAUUGAACACUGUUGGCAAUUGUAAUACAGUUGUAAGUAUUUGUGUGUCUAAACAUAGAAAAGGUACAGGAUAUAGUCUUACGGGACCACCAUCAUGUAUGCAGUUGCUUGUUGACCCAUGCAUGUAGGGUGGUGCGUCAUGGUAUCUUAAUAUUUUAGACCUCCAUUGACCACGGGUAACUGAAACUAUGGAAAGUGAAGCCUUGGACAAGGGGUACUGCUGUAUACCCAAUUAUAAAACUAAGCUUCAAUUUUGACAGCUUCAAAAUUAGAAAAACUUCAUAGGGAAGUGGUGGUAACUUAAAUGGGAUAUUGAUUCUGCUCCUACUCAUCCUUAGGUAGGGGUGUUUUUAAUGACAGUGGAUCACUAAGGUUGUGGUUCUAGAAUCUUGAAGUUAGCCCAAAACCUAAAUCUUAACCUCAGUCAGUUUGUUUGUUUGUUUGUUUGUUUAUUGAGACAGAGUCUCACUCUGUCACCCAGGCUGGAGUGCAGUGGCAUGAUCUGAGCUCACUGCAACGUCCACUUCCCGGGUUCAAGUGAUUGGCCUGCCCCAGCCUCCCAAGUAGCUGGGAUUACAGGCAUGCACCACCACGCCUGACUAGUUUUUGUAUUUUUAGUAGAGACAGGGUUUCACCAUGUUGGCCAGGCUGGUCUCGAACUCCUGACCUCGGGUGAUCCACCUGCCUUGGCCUCCCAGAGUGCUGGCAUUACAGGCAUGAGCUACCGUGCCUGGCCACCUCAGUCUUUUAGGAUGAUGGGUGAAUAUAAAUUUCAGUCUGUUUCUUUUCCAAGCUUUCUCAUGGCCUAGUCUGAAUCAGAUGGUUCAUAGUAAUUACCAUGGGUUCAGUCUUGAGUGUGAGAAGGGGAUUCUUAGAGACCCAGCAGUUUUCACUUCUGAAUCUUAGGUUCUCACUAGAACACAGGUUUAUCCUUGAAUCCAGCAGUUGGGUUUCUGUCCUUUAUGUGCUGUAUGGAUGAAGGAUGAGUUGUGGGUAUGAGUGAAUAACCUGAAGACCAGCCCUCAAGUGUGAAGUGUGAAGCAAAUAACCAAGUUUAAUCUUUUUUUUUUUUUUUUUUU